AUAAUGUGGUAAAUACAUAAGCAAAAAGUACCAUAGUAGUUUAUUUUCAUUAUCAAGUAUUAUGUACUGUGCAUAAUUGUACCUGUUAUACUUCUAUAUGAAUGGCAGUGCAGGUUUGUUCACACCAGCAUCACCACAAACACAUGAAUAAUGCAUUGUGCUAUGACUUUAAGAUGGCUGUGAUGUCACUAGACCACUAGGUGAUAGACAUUUUUUUAGCUCUAUUAUAACCUUAUGGGACCACCAUUGUAUAUUCAGUCUGUCAUUGACCAAAACAUGUUUAUUUGGCACAUGACUGUAUUUAUAGAAUUGUUGCAAGUGUGUGACCUGAAACUAACUGUAGUGGUCCACUGACUUUUGGAAAGGAUUCUUAGAAUCUGUAUGAUUUUCACCUCUGUAGUGUUUAUUUACAUGAACCAGCUCACAUGCCAACAAAUGCAUCAAAAAGCCUGCUUUUCCUGAUGGGGAGACUAUCAUCACUUAUUUCAUCAGAUUGUACCAGUAAAAAUUUAAGUUUAAACAACCAAACACUGAGAGUGGAACCAGGAGAAGUGAAUUCUCACUCCAAGGGCAAAGGCUUUCCACCUGGUACCACCUUCCCAAAUGGAGCCAGUGAGUGGGCAUUCCAAGGCGCCCAGCACCAUAUUAAUUGAGAAUGGAACUUACGUUUCAUUUUCAGGAAACUUCAUGGUGUUAUGGUCAACUUGCCGCACAACCGUGUUCAAAUCUGUCACCAACAGGUUCAUUAAAAACCUGGCCUGCUCGGGGAUUUGUGCCAGCCUGGUCUGUGUGCCCUUCGACAUCAUCCUCAGCACCAGUCCUCACUGUUGCUGGUGGAUCUACACCAUGCUCUUCUGCAAGGUCGUCAAAUUUUUGCACAAAGUAUUCUGCUCUGUGACCAUCCUCAGCUUCCCUGCUAUUGCUUUGGACAGGUACUACUCAGUCCUCUAUCCACUGGAGAGGAAAAUAUCUGAUGCCAAGUCCCGUGAACUGGUGAUGUACAUCUGGGCCCAUGCAGUGGUGGCCAGUGUCCCUGUGUUUGCAGUAACCAAUGUGGCUGACAUCUAUGCCACGUCCACCUGCACGGAAGUCUGGAGCAACUCCUUGGGCCACCUGGUGUACGUUCUGGUGUAUAACAUCACCACGGUCAUUGUGCCUGUGGUGGUGGUGUUCCUCUUCUUGAUACUGAUCCGACGGGCCCUGAGUGCCAGCCAGAAGAAGAAGGUCAUCAUAGCAGCGCUCCGGACCCCACAGAACACCAUCUCUAUUCCCUAUGCCUCCCAGCGGGAGGCCGAGCUGCACGCCACCCUGCUCUCCAUGGUGAUGGUCUUCAUCUUGUGUAGCGUGCCCUAUGCCACCCUGGUCGUCUACCAGACUGUGCUCAAUGUCCCUGACACUUCCGUCUUCUUGCUGCUCACUGCUGUUUGGCUGCCCAAAGUCUCCCUGCUGGCAAACCCUGUUCUCUUUCUUACUGUGAACAAAUCUGUCCGCAAGUGCUUGAUAGGGACCCUGGUGCAACUACACCACCGGUACAGUCGCCGUAAUGUGGUCAGUACAGGGAGUGGCAUGGCUGAGGCCAGCCUGGAACCCAGCAUACGCUCGGGUAGCCAGCUCCUGGAGAUGUUCCACAUUGGGCAGCAGCAGAUCUUUAAGCCCACAGAGGAUGAGGAAGAGAGUGAGGCCAAGUACAUUGGCUCAGCUGACUUCCAGGCCAAGGAGAUAUUUAGCACCUGCCUGGAGGGAGAGCAGGGGCCACAGUUUGCGCCCUCUGCCCCACCCCUGAGCACAGUGGACUCUGUAUCCCAGGUGGCACCGGCAGCCCCUGUGGAACCUGAAACAUUCCCUGAUAAGUAUUCCCUGCAGUUUGGCUUUGGGCCUUUUGAGUUGCCUCCUCAGUGGCUCUCAGAGACCCGAAACAGCAAGAAGCGGCUGCUUCCCCCCUUGGGCAACACCCCAGAAGAGCUGAUCCAGACAAAGGUGCCCAAGGUAGGCAGGGUGGAGCGGAAGAUGAGCAGAAACAAUAAAGUGAGCAUUUUUCCAAAGGUGGAUUCCUAGCAAGGAUUGUAAAUUCUUGGAAGCAACGGGGAGCUUCCAUAUUCCCACCAGAGUGUGGGAAUGCUGUGGCCAUGUGAUUGUAUGAUCUCCUUGCAACUCAGUGUGAGUUGAUUCCUCCAAUAUGGGCCAGAUGCUUUUGAAUGAUAGGGAAAUCUACAUAAAAUCCAGUGUCCUCUUUAUUGAGGGAGUAUAUGUAUCCAUCUCAGUGAUCCAUGUCCUUAGUGAAGUCCACAUUAUUCUCUGUGGGGACAAGAGCUGGGCAGUUUUGAAUGGGUCUUGAGGUGGGUACCCCAUGUGCACUUUCUGAGGAUGCCUCACUUCCCUGGGCUCUGCAGAGAACACACAGAGAGAAGACUUUCAGAGCUCACAGGAGCAGGGAGCAGGAGCACUCUAAGGGAAUUCCAAGAUCAUGAUGGAGCAUGGUGGCUCCAGAGAAAAUGCCUGUUUGAUGAACUUAAACAUGUCAAACAUUUUCUGUUGAGAAGGUAGGGAUUUGGUGUCUUACACUGUUUCUCUGGAAGCCCCAGUCAUAUGACUCACUGUUUCUCCUGAUACCCUUCGUCCCUUUCAUUGGGAUGUAGGUAAGGAAUGACGAUUCCUCACCUAUGGUACACAUGGCGAUAGAUGUGCCCGGGAGUAAGGGAGAUAUUUUGUCCUUGAUAAUUCUGAUUUUCCCUUGGCAUCACCAACGCCUCAGAGAGAUACACCUGCACCCUCCAGUCAGGGUCAGUGUUGGCUGGAAAACACUGAAAAGUCUUCGCUCUGUCUUUCACCUUAAAUUGUGUUUUCUCAACAAAUGAGAGAGAAGCUUACGGGGGAGAUGCCUGAGAGAUGCCUAUGGCGCUGUAGUUUUUUUUUCUUCCCUAUGAUCUCACAUGAAAGGUGCUAUGUAACAACCAGUAUGAGUCAAAUAUAUUGAAAAAAUCAUCUUAUGCAAACUUUAGGAAUUAAAAGGUAUUUUUAAAAUGGAGAGUUAGUGUAAGCUGGGUCCUUUGGAAACAUCAAACUGAAAAGGCCUGAUUUGGAAAGGUGACUCUGCCCAAAAGGUUGGCAAGAAUCUGACAAAGAUGGUUUCCUUCCGAGGAAGACUCCGGAACUCAGGUGUGGCCAGUCUCCUUUUCAGUCUGUUUGUACAGCUGCGGUUCUCUCUUAAUUUUGGACACAGAGGAGGAACAGAACAGGGAGAAAUAAUCAUUGUAGAGUGCCAAGGCAACAUCUGACCCAGAUGAGCUCUUCACUUCCUCCUUCCCUGUCGUUGUAGAGCCAGACUGGGUAGAAGAGGGAGGGCAGUGUCCUCAACUCAUCAGCCUCACAAGCAAUUUGGGACCCCUCUGGGGUGGAUUUCACCAGGUUGAAUUAGAACCGCAGAUAAUACUUCCCUGUUAGUGAGGACAAACCAAGCGCCAGCUCUGCCCUUUUCUCUAGAGUGUUGUGUUCUUGCUCUUGGUACUUACAGGAGCUAGUCUGGUGCCUUGAGCAAGCUUGAAGGGAAGUGGGUGUCCUCACCAGCAAACUUCCACAUCUCAACUCGUGCCCUCUUUUGGCCACACUGGCCCCGUCUCUUGGAGGGAGCCCAGACCCUGUAGGGAGUUUUGUUUUCCUUUCUUCUCUUGGGUGUGGUGUCUUGUGUUUCUGAAUGUGAACCCAAAGACCCUACCCCUGGAGAGGAAGCACCUUCCUCUUUGUGUUGGUCUCCUCAUAGCACUGUUUGCUCACAGCAGAAACGGGGCUGCCACAGCCUCCUGCGGCUCUGCUGCCUUCUGGGCCCUGCGUGCAUGGCAUCUAUAGCUCCUUGCCCUGAUAGUCAAUGCUGUGGCCCUUCAAGCUUGUCUUUCAAAGCUUUCACAAUCAUUACAACUUUUAUCAAGGGGAAUAAUAAUCUCUAGGAAAAUUAUGUCCACUUUAGGAGAAUCUGUCAAGUGUAGCCACUUUGGUGUUGUUCUGAUAAUAUACUGUAUAUGUACAACUUAAUAAAUUUUGAUGAGGCAGAAUCUGGUUGGGUAUGUUUCUUAUAUAUGUUUGAAGCAGAUGGCUGACUACUAACAGGUCAUUGCCAGGUGUAUUUCUAUACUCUUUGAAGAAUAACAUUUUAAUAAAAAAUUGAAAAGCAGUUUCUGAACUCAA